AGAUUGCUCAUGUAACUCUUGAGUUUACAUGUAAUCAACAUAUGCUCAUUGAAAACGGGAUUGCUUCAAGAGGACUUUGAGUGCAGGGUGAUUAGGUAAGUAAAAGAUGUAAAAAGGUAGAAAAUUUUUGUCACUUGAGUCUAAAUAAUUGUUCUUAUAAGUGCCAACGCCUGUUUCUGUUAGGCUCAGAAGAUCAAAGGAUUUGGCUCUUUUAAAAUAUAGAAAGCUCUAGCUUCAGCUAGAAUUUAGGCCUUUAGUAAUAGCCCUAAUUUUUAUGAAGCCAUUUUGUUCCAGUGAUCUUUUGGUGAGAGAUGCUAUGUAAGUACUAUUCUUCAGAAUUAGGUGUCUUUUUACCCUAAUGAAAUAAUUUAGAUUGCUUUUGAUACAGGUAAAACAAAUAUCCUGGCUUCCAUAAUUGUAGAAAAAACUUCAUAUAGGAAUCCUUGUUGUAUCAAAGUAGCACCUGAUGGGAAUGAACAGACAGGAAUGGAUGAAGGAUAGCAGUUUGCGUUCCAUUUCAAGCCUAUGGGCUCACACAUUUAUUCAGAUAAGAACACCACCUUUCACUAGAUAAACUCCAACAGUAUUCAUGCAUACUUUUGAAUGGCAUGUAGGAAAUGUUUGAUAGGUACAUAAUGUAUUCACUUCAGGUCACUAAUGUAAUACGGGGUCGUGCUCCUUAGUGUUGACAGAUCACCUAUGGUUCUCCAAAAUGAACAUUCUAGUACAGGAGGUCUAGGGAGGAACCUGAGAGUAUACUAAUGCCUAGGAACUUUCUCUGGAGUGGCAAGAGCAGUGGGAAGAAUUAUGUCAAUAGCUACAGAAAUAAGGGAGUAAGAACAAGUCAUCUCUCUAGUGAAUUCUUCUUCACUUUACUGAGAUAAACAUACAUGUUAAUGAGCUUGAGUUUUCCCAAAAGUAUAAUUCUUCUGGUUCUUCUAAGAAAAUGGCACUCCCUGGAAACAAGGAAGAACCAAAUUUAUUCGCCUUUGUAGCAGUUGGGAAAGUUAGUGCUAGGAAGUCUUCUUGAUUUAUAGUAGGCUUUAAUCUGGAUAUUGCUGGUAAAAGUUUAUUCUAAAACCUGAACUCUGGAUAAGUAAUACAAAAAGCUUCUCAACCUUCCAAGCAAAAUUGAGAGCUUUCAGGUUAUGUGAGUAAUUUGGUCUCUUGGGUGCUUAAUUCAUUCCUUGAAGCUCAUUUUUGUGAUCUCUUCCAAGAUUGCAUUUGCUUGGAGGUAGGGAGUUAGACAAGAUGGUAUGAGGUCCCUAAAUUUUGACUUUCCAAGCAAAAUUGGACAGUGGUUCCUAAAUUGCUAACAUCCUCGUUUCUUCCUAAGGCUUCUCAUGUUUCAUAUAUAGUAGCCUUCCCAAAGUCCCAUUUCCCACCCCCCCCCCCCCCCCAACCCAUGUAGAGAGAACGAACCUGUCUCCCUUCCUGUACAGAGUACGGGAUCCUUCAACUUUCACACAGGCUGCAGUGUCUGCCACACAUUUAGCUCAACUUUUUUUUAGCCUUAAAGUGAUGUCCGCUGCAUCUGUCGCUGGGUUGCACCUUGUGGAUUUAGUUUGCAUAAAUUUUCUCAGCUUAAACAAAGUUAACAUUGAAUAGAGUAAGCUUACCAUAAAGGGCUUAAUAAAUGCCAUGCAUGUCUACAUUCGGUGUGGAAAUUGAGCUAGUCAGGUUGAUAUUUAACAUUGUAGGUUCUUUGUUAAUUUAUAUGAAAUAAUGGUUAUCAUUUAACUCUUUAGGUUAGCUUUGUACAUAGCAUCUCACUUUGCACAACAACCCUGCAAGGUAAGUAUUGUUAUUCUUGUGCUACAAAUGAAGUUGACUGAGAGGAGGAGUACCACGUCCAAGGUCACACAGCUAUUAAAUGGCAGGGCUGGGAUACUGGCCUGUGACUCAGAACUUGAUGCUUUCCCCCCACGCCACGCAUGCCAGGUUGCCCUUCCUUUCAGAAAUGGUGGAAGUCCUGCAAAAUGCAAUAAACUGAAGUAAUGUAGCUUCUAUUAAUACAAAGUAAAUAACUCAGAUUUACUGGAUUUUAAACCUUAUUCCUUGGGUAAACAAUCUGUGACUGACUUCACACCAAAUAUUUGUUGGCGGAGGAUUUGGACUUUAGGGAUAAAAGUGGAUACAUUUUUUAUUUUACAAACUCUGUAUUUGAACUUAAUUAUUGGCUCUUCAAUUUUACGUUACCAGCUUUUUUUUUUUUUUUUUUUUUUAAUGAAUUUGAUUUACAUCAUGGUCAAACAAAAAUUGUUGAGCAGGGAAAAUAAACUGCUUUCUGGAUUCCUUCUUGAAUUUUCUCAUGUGCCCUAGAGAAAAUGUGUUCCACAUUAAGGUGUUACUUUUUCCAGGGGUGUGUUCAUUUAAAAAGAAUGAAGCCAGGCAAUGUUUAUUUUUCUUUUACCUAUAAAUAAAUGAAUGGAUUAAUCAUUGUAUACUUGACUCCCAUGUUGGUAGGGAUUUUAGAUAGGAGGCUAUUUCUUGUCUGUGCUUCUCAAUACCCCAUAAGCAGUUGCUUCAUGGAUGUAUAUACUAAUAAGCAGUGAAAGAAAGUGCAUGUUCAAAGAAUACAACAAGGAGUCUGGAUAUUUUGCAAUCAUCUUUAUAUAUUACGGUGCUCUGAAUUAAAAGCUAAAAGUUACUGGGUAUGUCUGACACCUUAGUGCUUUAUCUUUGUUCUACUAAUUUUCUGUGCCCCAAUCCCACUUAACCCUAGCCUCAUUCCUUAUCUGUAAGAUAGGGGAUAAUACCACUGUAAGGUUAUUAUUAAGAUUGAAUAAGGAUAAAAUUUAUAAUGGGUUUUAGCAAAUGGCAGAAAAUAUUUUCUGAAGAAAACCAAGUGCUAUUAAAAAAACAUCACAAGCCUUGGGCUUACUUUGGGAUUUUAAAAACCAAGAGAAAAUGGAUGGCUGAACUUUCAAACAUUUGGUAAAUAUUAUAGUACUGUAGUUCAGAGCUCUGGAUUCUUUGCAUUUUGCCUGCUGGGUGAGAAGGAAUAAAAGUUUGUGCCUUUUUUUUUUUUUAAUCACUUUAAUUUCAAAACAAUGUGUUUAACCAUUUGUGGGAGUAAUUUUCAUUUUGUGAGCCUGAAGCAUUUUGAUUCAGUGGGAAUUUCUGGUGAUUUAUAUCUGGAAUAGAAGUGAGCUUAAGUUUAGCUAUUCUAACGUUGAAAAAGGAAGCAAUGUUUCUAUUGGAUUCUAAAGUAUAUUUUCAAAAAUAUUCUGAAGUAUUUGUAUAUCUUAAACUUGGAGUUAAGACAGCUUAGCUUUGAAGAUAAGAGAAACUAGAUGUGUGCAUUUUCUAUCCAGAUGUGUUUGUUGCUGGAACUAAAUGAAACAGUACAUGGUAACCCUUGAAAGGUUUUAAACUUGUUUCUGUAACUGCUAAUCUACAUACUCUCAAGUCACUAACCUUCCUCUUUGAUCUCUUUGUAGGCUGACCAACUGACUGAAGAGCAGAUUGCAGAAUUCAAAGAAGCUUUUUCACUAUUUGACAAAGAUGGUGAUGGAACUAUAACAACAAAGGAAUUGGGAACUGUAAUGAGAUCUCUUGGGCAGAAUCCCACAGAAGCAGAGUUACAGGACAUGAUUAAUGAAGUAGAUGCUGAUGGUAAUGGCACAAUUGACUUCCCUGAAUUUCUGACAAUGAUGGCAAGAAAAAUGAAAGACACAGACAGUGAAGAAGAAAUUAGAGAAGCAUUCCGUGUGUUUGAUAAGGAUGGCAAUGGCUAUAUUAGUGCUGCAGAACUUCGCCAUGUGAUGACAAACCUUGGAGAGAAGUUAACAGAUGAAGAAGUUGAUGAAAUGAUCAGGGAAGCAGAUAUUGAUGGUGAUGGUCAAGUAAACUAUGAAGAGUUUGUACAAAUGAUGACAGCAAAGUGAAGACCUUGUACAGAAUGUGUUAAAUUUCUUGUACAAAAUUGUUUAUUUGCCUUUUCUUUGUUUGUAACUUAUCUGUAAAAGGUUUCUCCCUACUGUCAAAAAAAUAUGCAUGUAUAGUAAUUAGGACUUCAUUCCUCCAUGUUUUCUUCCCUUAUCUUACUGUCAUUGUCCUAAAACCUUAUUUUAGAAAAUUGAUCAAGUAACAUGUUGCAUGUGGCUUACUCUGGAUAUAUCUAAGCCCUUCUGCACAUCUAAACUUAGAUGGAGUUGGUCAAAUGAGGGAACAUCUGGGUUAUGCCUUUUUUAAAGUAGUUUUCUUUAGGAACUGUCAGCAUGUUGUUGUUGAAGUGUGGAGUUGUAACUCUGCGUGGACUAUGGACAGUCAACAAUAUGUACUUAAAAGUUGCACUAUUGCAAAACGGGUGUAUUAUCCAGGUACUCGUACACUAUUUUUUUGUACUGCUGGUCCUGUACCAGAAACAUUUUCUUUUAUUGUUACUUGCUUUUUAAACUUUGUUUAGCCACUUAAAAUCUGCUUAUGGCACAAUUUGCCUCAAAAUCCAUUCCAAGUUGUAUAUUUGUUUUCCAAUAAAAAAAUUACAAUUUACCCAAUGGUUGCUCUGCAUCUGAGUCAUUUAACUGUUGAAGUCUAAUAAUUUUGAAAAUAAAAUAUGGCAUUGGUUUCUGCUUGGUA